GGCAGGGCAGGCAGCUGUCUCAGUCUAACUCUGGCUGGGAAAGGUAAGGAUCUUUGCUUUGCUUUUUGAAAGAUCUGGGAAGGAAAUGUUGAAUGUCUAUGGGGGUUAGGGGCAUAGAUAUAAUUCAUGCAUUGGAGGCUUUGAGAAAAGUUCUCCAAACUUAAAGGAGUCUCCUAAAGCCAUGUGCUUUAGAAAGAACUAGAGAGAUUUCCUCUUCUUUGUGAAAAUAGAGGGCUCGCAGAAAUAAGGCUGGUUGCAUUGUGGAUGAAAUUUUGCAUUUGGGGGCAGGUGUCCCCAAAGGAUGCCCAGGGGUGUUUAAUACUUUGUAGACACAGAGUGGAAGGAGGAAUAAACAUUCAGAAACAACAGGCAUAGAUCACUAGGAAUUCUCUUUGAAUUUCAAUUUGAAGAGGUAAAGUCAGUUAAAGCUGCAUGUGUCAGUGGUUAGGAUGACAGGCUUCUAUUCUUCUGAUACAAUGUCUGCUUUAUACCAAAACUUUCUACCUCUUUGAAUUUAAAAUACAAAUCAUUGGUUGUCUACUCAGAGUCUAGAGAUGUGUACCUGUGUAUCAAGGCAGGUGCACACACCCUGUGGAGGAGCAUUGGUGUGAAUGAGGCACCUGAGCCUGACAAGGUUGAAGAAAGCUUUGGUAUUGGAAGUGAUGACAGAUUUGUGCUCCUAGGACACAGACACACUCACUGCGCCUCAUUAUAGACUCAGUCAAGGGCUUACUAUGAAAAAAGCUGCCAUUGUCCUCUCUCUAGACGUUCAAUGUUUGCACCUUUAGCUUUGGUAACAGGAAAGCAUGCUUUUCAACAGAAUAAGGUGAUAUUCAGAGCUUCAGUGCAGUUAUUGGGCUAUCUUGCAGGCAAAGUGGUACUAGAAAAUAGAGGGGAAUUGCCCUCAAGGGCCAGAGUUUGCAGGUGAGAAGACAGCUCUGUUAAGGAGCUUCUCAAGAACCUCCAUUGUACGUAGCCAGCGGCCCCCAUCUUACCAUCUUCCGGGGGCAACUUUGGCAAGUUCUGAAAUGCCCUGGUUCUAAGUAUUCCUGACCCUCAACACCAAGUGACGGUACUCCUCAGAUAUGAAAGCUGUCUCUUUAGGUCUGACAUUUUUAAAGUGUGAGGAUCAUGGUGACCAAGGCCUCCAGGUACUUGCCAUGACUCCCCCAACCUCAGGGACUUUUCAACUUUAUUUUUUAUAAGGACAUAACCCUCUCUCUGGCUUUCAUUCCAGAAUAAACAACUUCUGGUCCCUCUCUUUUUGUGACAAGUCAUCAGGGUAUUGCUACAAGGCAAGGCUGGAGAGAGUGUGCUGUGGUAGAGGAGAGGCGAGAUGUUUGAGAACAUCCAAGCCCUUUGCCAGCUAUUAGAGAAAUCUAACAAUUUGAGAGAAAGAUGGAAAACAAAUCUCUUCCAAGAGUUAAUUUGGAUUUGUGGUUCACAGUAUUAAUUAGAAGAGGUUAUUAACACUUGUGCAGAUGAAAAAAUGGAGGAUGUAAACUUUUAACUACAGAGUGUAGGAUGAGCUCCCAGUAUUAUCUUUUCUCCUCAAAAAGACAAUCUUGGGCUUUAUAUGUUUCAAGGUUUUAAAAAUUUCACAGUUUGUCUGUAAGAAAGCAUAAACCUAUAAAGUCACUUACAGGUUUAUGGGGUGGGAAAUAGAUGUUUAACUUUAUUGUUUAAGUAUGAUGUGUCAAGUUGUAUAUGUUUGAAUGUUUAAAAUACCUUGAUCCUUAAAGUGGGCCAAGGAACAGAGGUCUCAACAUAGGUAGGGAGCUUGUUACAGACUUACUGAAUCAGAAUCUAAAUUUAACAAUCUCCCCAAAUGAUAUAUAUAUCCAUUAAAGAUUAGGGUUCAAACCAAGGGUGUCUCUGUUACUGGGUGAUCUUUGUUAAAUUACUUAACCUCUCUGAGCCUGUUUCCUCAUUUAUGAACUAGUGAGAAUUAACAUUAAUAUGUGACAUUUCUUAAUAUUGUGCCAUGUCCACAGUAGGUGCUCUAUAAAUGGUAGCAAUUAUCAUGAUGAUGAUAAUCUUGGUGCUGCUAAAGUUACCUCCUUGCAAAAGCAGUAAACAAUCAUGUUUAAAUCAAUAUAACUGGCUUUCCCCCUUAACCACAAACAUUUGUGCCUCCCACCCUCAUUCCUAAAUGAAUUAACACUCAACAAGUGGGGUUUUAAGCUUCAGAUGACUAUCACGCACAUAUAAAGAAUAAUGGAAAACCUAGGAACAUGGAUUUUUGCUGGCUUAGAGACUGAAUUCAGCUGCCUGAUGACUUCACAGCUGUUUCUGCCACCCUAGAGUAUCUGUCCCCUCGGCUCUGUCCCCUCAGCCGGGUCUGCAACGCUGACUCUGGGAUUUUCUUAUAAAAAUGCCUGAUGGACGGGAGGAAGAUCUGGAGGUCGGCGGGGGAAAAAAUGAGUCAUUCAAAUUCACAAAGCAGUCCGCUUAGUAAAUGCUGCAAGAGAAAAACCUUGCUGUUAGAGGCUCUUUCCCAGAAGUUGGACGAAGAGGCUCAGGCGUUGCUGUUUCUUGUCUUCCAAGUCAAGUGGUUACUCUGGUAAUGGAUUGCCUCUCUCCGAGCUUUCACCCUGGUGAGACUGUCCAGAUCUAGUCUGUAAACCCAGCUUAGAAGCACUGUUGUAAAAAUGACUGAAGAGCCCAUCAAGGAGAUCCUGGGAGCCCCAAAGGCUCACAUGGCAGCGACGAUGGAGAAGAGCCCCAAGAGUGAAGUUGUGAUCACCACAGUCCCUCUGGUCAGUGAGAUUCAGUUGAUGGCUGCUACAGGGGGUACCGAGCUCUCCUGCUACCGCUGCAUCAUCCCCUUUGCUGUGGUUGUCUUCAUCGCCGGCAUCGUGGUCACCGCGGUGGCUUACAGCUUCAAUUCCCAUGGGUCUAUUAUCUCCAUCUUUGGCCUGGUUGUUCUGUCAUCUGGACUUUUUUUACUAGCCUCCAGUGCCUUGUGCUGGAAAGUGAGACAAAGGAGCAAGAAAGCCAAGAGACGGGAGAGUCAAACAGCUCUCGUGGCAAAUCAGAGAAGCUUGUUUGCUUGAGACUGAAUACGACCAAAUGGGCCAUUGGGCCUGGAAAACGUGCUCUGACUUUGUCACCCAAUUCACCCAGAACCAUGGUGGGAGAGAACAGACUUGGCGUUGGAGCAGACUGGAAGAAUGGGGGUGGGAGGGUGGAGGGGCUUCUCCUUUGUGAGGAAUGACUCAUGUCUUCUUUAACGACAAACUUAACCCUAAGGGCUACUUCUGAGACUGAAAAAUCAGCUUUCUAUUUACAUGAAACACUUUGGGGGUCAUGGGAGUGCACAGCAUUAGACAGUAUUUGGUUCACCCUGUAAAGUAGCCAAGAAAAGAUGAGAAAAAUCAAGAUAGGCCUGGCACACUAGACAUUUGCCUCCAAAAGAAAUAACCUACAGUCUUAAGAUGUAUCAUAAAAAUGUUCUGCCAAGGAUCUAAAUUACCUUGGGUUUCGCAUAUGUCUAUGAAAUUCUGUGAUAAUUUUUUUCAAUACAUUGAUUCACUGGCGUCUGUUUUCAUUUUAUACUUUUAAUAACUCAUCACUGGUGGUACUUUAUCUUGAAAAGUAAUAUUUUUUAUAUUUUAACAUUGGACAGUGUUAGCCAGUUGUAAUGAUGUAUCAGAAGUAAAGAAAAACCCAUUAAAGUUAUAGCUAAUAGAUGCUGUUGGGGGUUAAAUUAAUAGUAAAAUAAUCCAAUAUAGCACUUUUGAUGAUUUUUAUAUAAAAGUCAACUGUACAUUUCAUUCAGAAUAAUAAAUACUUAUUGCUGCUAAAACUUCUUAAAUGGUUGUUUCUGCUAUAGUUAUUUCUAUUGCAGUUCCAAAUUGCCAUCUUCCCUUGUCUCAUUUGCAAGUUCUCAAUUGUAUUUCUCUCAAAUGGACAGGUUCCUUCUUUACUGGAGGAUUUUUGUUUUUAUCAUAUUGGUUUUUCAUUACUUCUGAAUAGUCUUAAUUACGUUUACUAAAUUCUAAAGGAUUUCUGUGCUAUUAUAAUUAGGAAAUCAACGUCUUUGGUCAGGAACUUUAUAAUGUGCUAUUAAAUGUAUAUUACAUUUUUGUGGAA